CUGCUAUACAACUGAGCCUACCUUUCUUGAAACCAUGAGCUUUGAUAACAACUACCAUGGUGGCCAGGGCUAUGCCAAAGGAGGCCUGGGCUGCAGCUAUGGCUGUGGUCUUAGCGGCUAUGGCUAUGCCUGCUACUGCCCAUGGUGUUAUGAAAGAUCUUGGUUUUCUGGCUGCUUCUGAGAAAUUAGAGAUUGCUGAUCUGUUUAGGCCAUUCUCUUAUGAGCUAUGUUUUCUUCCCGUGUUUUUUUCUGUUCAAAGAGUGACAACUAAAAUUUAGCCCACAUUGCCAAGUCAG